CCAGGCUCCGGUCUGACUGUAGUGGUUUGACUUUGUCUACACCGGCGGUGGCAGGGAGGACCCUUAGUAUUUCGCAAAGAAUGAGGAAGGGAGGGCAGGAUCUGAAUAGGGUGCUUCGCGGCCCUUAGGUGUAUCCCGCUCACGGCCAGAAAGCUUCGAGGGAAACUGGAGACCUUCCUCGGGGUGUGGCAGCUGCCGGCUUGGACUUCACCAGCGACCCUGGACUUGCCCUGUAUGAUUUGGCCCAAAGUGGAAUGCUGUCACUUUAAGACUGCAGUGGAAGCACCACUUGGAAUGAAAUUGGACAAGAAAAUGGAAGUCUUCAUCCCACUCUCAACUUCUGCAGCCUCUAGUGGGCCAUGGGCUCAUUCCUUAUUUGCUUUUAUACCCUCCUGGCCUAAGAAGAACUUAUUUAAAAGAGAGUCUCCUAUAACACACCGCCUGUAUGGGGACAUUUCAAGAGAAGUUCAAGGGACUUCUGAAAAUGGAGUAAUUUUUCAGAAAUGUGCACUGGUGUCUGGGUCGAGUGAAGCACAGACAGCCCGCAUAUGGCUGCUUGUUAACAACACCAAGACAACCUCGUCAGCCAACCUCUCGGAGCUGCUCUUGCUGGACAGCAUUGCUGGUCUCACCAUUUGGGACUCUGUGGGAAACAGGACCUCGGAAGGAUUCCAGGCUUUUAGCAAGAAGUUUCUGCAAGUGGGAGAUGCCUUUGCUGUCAGCUACGCAGCCACGCUCCAGGCUGGAGACCUCGGGAACGGGGAGAGCCUCAAGCUUCCUGCCCAACUCACCUUUCAGAGCUCGUCACGGAACAGAACACAGCUGAAAGUGCUUUUUUCCAUAACAGCAGAAGAAAACGUAACGGUUCUGCCGCACCACGGCCUCCACGCAGCAGGGUUCUUCAUUGCCUUCCUCCUCUCCCUUGUGCUGACCUGGGCUGCCCUCUUCCUCAUGGUUCGCUAUCAGUGUCUGAAGGGAAACAUGCUCACCAGACAUCGGGUUUGGCAGUAUGAGAGCAAGCUGGAACCCUUGCCGUUCACCUCAGCUGAUGGCGUGAAUGAGGACCUUUCCCUUAACGACCAAAUGAUAGACAUUCUGUCUUCCGAGGACCCUGGGAGCAUGCUUCAAGCCUUAGAAGAGUUGGAGAUUGCAACCCUGAAUCGGGCAGAUGCAGAUCUGGAGGCUUGUCGAACACAAAUCAGCAAGGAUAUCAUUGCCCUUCUGCUGAAAAAUCUCACCAGCAGUGGCCACCUCUCACCCCAAGUAGAGAGAAAAAUGAGUGCUGUUUUCAAAAAGCAGUUUCUAUUGCUGGAAAAUGAAAUACAAGAGGAGUACGAUCGGAAGAUGGUGGCAUUGACAGCUGAAUGUGACCUGGAAACAAGAAAGAAGAUGGAAAACCAGUACCAGAGAGAGAUGAUGGCAAUGGAGGAAGCAGAAGAGUUGCUGAAACGUGCUGGUGAGAGGUCUGCUGUAGAGUGCAGCAACCUUCUGCGGACCCUCCAUGGCCUGGAACAGGAGCACUUGAGGAAGUCUCUCGCUUUGCAACAAGAAGAAGACUUUGCCAAAGCUCACAGACAGCUGGCUGUUUUCCAGAGAAAUGAACUGCACAGUAUCUUUUUUACCCAGAUAAAAAGUGCUAUUUUCAAAGGGGAAUUGAAACCAGAGGCAGCUAAAAUGCUGCUGCAAAAUUAUUCUAAAAUACAGGAGAAUGUAGAAGAGUUAAUGGACUUUUUCCAGGCUAGUAAGAGGUAUCAUCUAAGUAAAAGAUUUGGCCACAGGGAAUAUCUGGUCCAGAACCUCCAGUCAUCAGAGACCCGUGUGCAGGGCCUUCUGAGCACCGCUGCAGCCCAGCUGACUCACCUCAUUCAGAAGCACGAGAGAGCAGGGUACCUGGAUGAAGACCAAAUGGAAAUGCUAUUGGAGCGGGCUCAGACAGAAGUCUUUUCAAUCAAGCAGAAGUUGGACAAUGACUUAAAGCAGGAAAAGAAAAAGCUCCACCAAAAAUUAAUAACUAAGAGAAGACGAGAGUUGCUACAAAAGCACAGGGAGCAGCGUAGGGAGCAGGCGUCCGUCGGCGAGGCCUUCCGAACGGUUGAGGAUGCCGGCCAGUACCUGCACCAGAAGAGGAGCCUGAUGGAGGAGCACGGUGCCACCCUGGAGGAGCUGCAGGAGCGUCUGGACCAGGCCGCCCUGGACGAUCUCAGGACCCUGACCCUUUCGCUGUUUGAAAAGGCCACCGACGAGCUGCGGCGCCUGCAGAACUCAGCCAUGACCCAGGAGCUGCUCAAGCGUGGGGUGCCCUGGCUCUUCCUGCAGCAGAUCCUGGAGGAGCACGGCAAGGAGAUGGCUGCACGGGCCGAGCAGCUGGAGGGGGAGGAGAGGGACAGGGACCAGGAGGGUGUCCAGAGCGUGAGGCAGAGACUGAAGGAUGACGCUCCUGAGGCCGUGACAGAGGAGCAGGCAGAGCUGCGACGCUGGGAGCACCUGAUCUUCAUGAAGCUCUGCUCCUCAGUCUUCUCCCUGUCUGAAGAGGAGCUGCUCAGGAUGAGGCAGGAGGUCCAUGGCUGCUUUGCUCAGAUGGACAGGAGCUUGGCCCUCCCCAAGAUCCGGGCCCGAGUUCUGCUGCAGCAAUUUCAGACUGCGUGGCGAGAAGCAGAGUUCGUGAAGCUGGACCAGGCCGUGGCUGCCCCUGAGCUGCAGCAACAGUCCAAGGUGAGAAAGUCACGGUCCAAGAGUAAAAGCAAGGGAGAGCUUCUGAAGAAGUGCAUCGAAGACAAAAUUCACCUCUGUGAGGAACAGGCCUCUGAAGACCUGGUGGAAAAGGUUCGAGGUGAAUUGCUGCGGGAGAGAGUGCAGCGGAUGGAGGCACAGGAGGGAGGCUUUGCACAGUCGCUUGUUGCUCUGCAGUUCCAGAAGGCGUCCCGGGUGACCGAGACUCUGUCGGCCUACACCGCCCUCCUCAGCAUCCAGGACUUGCUCCUGGAAGAGCUGAGUGCAUCUGAGAUGCUGACCAAGUCGGCCUGCACACAGAUCCUGGAGUCGCACAGCCGGGAGCUCCAGGAGUUGGAGAGGAAGCUGGAGGACCAGCUGGUGCAGCAGGAGGCAGCCCAGCAGCAGCAGGCCCUGGCGAGCUGGCAGCAGUGGGUGGCCGAUGGGCCCGGGAUUCUGAACGAACCUGGGGAGGUGGAUUCUGAAAGGCAGGUCUCUACUGUCCUGCACCAAGCCCUGAGCAAGAGCCAGACAUUACUGGAGCAACAUCAGCAGUGUUUGAGAGAGGAACAACAGAACAGUGUCGUGCUAGAAGACUUGUUGGAAAACAUGGAGGCAGACACCUUUGCAACCCUGUGCAGCCAGGAGCUGAGACUGGCAUCGUACCUGGCGAGGAUGGCCAUGGUGCCCGGGGCCACGCUUCGCCGGCUCCUGAGUGUGGUACUGCCCACAGCCUCACAGCCUCAGCUGCUGGCCCUGCUGGAUUCGGCCACCGAGAGACAUGUGGACCACGCAGCUGAGAGCGAUGGCGGAGCGGAGCAGGCCGACGUGGGCAGGCGGAGGAAACACCAGAGCUGGUGGCAAGCCUUAGAUGGCAAACUGCGAGGAGAUCUGAUAAGCAGAGGAUUAGAAAAGAUGCUGUGGGCCCGCAAGAGAAAGCAGAGAUGCUAUGCUAAGUGCCAGACCACUGUGAACUGCAGAGGAAAAACCAGGGUAUCAGAACUCUUCCACCGGUGGGGAUAGUAGAGGCCACAAAGCCUCCAUCACUCAACGCAAUUGCAUCUAAAGAAUAAUUUUCUGCAGACCACAUGGAGGUGAGAUGUUUGAGGUUUCUGAACAGGAAGCCCAAACAUGUUAAUUUGAUACAUUAGCAGGGGCUUAUUAUUUUCCCGUAACAAGGUCACAGGAAAUUUAUUAGCACUGUAUCACAAUCCUCUGGAAGAAAAAUCGUCAGAGGUCACAUUAACCCUUUAGUUCCCGCUGCUGUGAGGAAGGUUUUGUUGGGCAAUGCUUUAACUUUUGAUGGUCACUGAAACAUCCCAGUCUCUCACCUUUAUAUGAUGCCUCUGUUUUCAUCUAUCUAUCCAUCCAUCCAUCUAUCCACCCAUCCAUCCACUCACUCGCUGAACCAAUAGUUGCUGGAGCAUCUGCUGUGGGCACUGCUGCAGAAUCGGGGAUGUGGCAGUGAACAGCACCCACAAAUUCCCACCCUUCAAUGAGUUAACAUUCUCAUGUCAUUCUCUCACAGCUUCAUACAGCAACUCUCUAAAAUCAGUGUCAUUUUUCAUAUGAAAAAUUGAGGUGCCAGGCAUGCAGCCUGUAGCCCUUUCCCAGUCUUUUCUCCACAGAGCAGCCAGGCUGAUCUUUUUUAAAAAUGUAAAUCACUCCCUGCUUAAAAUCUUCUAGUGCCUCCUCAUCGCUCUUAAGAAUAAAAUCCAAAUUCCUUACCAGAGCCUAUGAGACCGUGAAGGAUAUGCCUCUUGGCUCCCUCUGUGACCUCAUCUCCCCCUUGCUCAUCGCAAUUCUGCCAUGUUUGUCUUCUCUUUGCUCUCCCAGGACUCUGAGCAGGGUCCUGCCUCAGGACCUUUGCACCAUCUAUUUCUGAACACUCUGCUCUCUGUGUAUUUCCUUGGCUGAUUUCUGCCAUUUGGGUUUCAGCUCAGAUAUCACCUCCUCCAGUAGGCCUUUUGGGACUUGUCCACCCCUCUUUCCCCCAUGCCCUGUUUUCUUUCUCACAUGGCUGUGGCAGUCAGCUUUCUUAGCGGCAAUAUGGACUCCAGCAAACGAACUCUGGCAGAUACAUGGGUAGUGCAGGGGAACAAGCUCUUAUCCACAGCUAGAUGCCCUGGCGGCUCUUCUGCCCCUUACUGGCUGCAGGGCGUGAGACAAGCAUCUUAAUCUCUCCAGUCCUUGGAACAUGGAAACCAGACCAUGUCUUUCCUCUGCUCAAAGCCUUUUAAGGGCUUCCCAUCCCAGGCAGAGAAAAAGCCACGUUCCUUUCUAUGCCCUGAAAAGCCAUCCAACUGGACCCAUUCCUUGCCCGACCUCUCCUCCCACUCCACCCCCCACUGGCUCUGCUCCAGCCACUUCUGCCCUUGCUGUUCCUUGAGCAGCCAGGACUGUGGCUGCCUCCAGGCCUUUGCACUUGCUGCUUUCUGUCUCUGGAAUGCUCUUCCUCCAACACCCACGUGGCUUUUAAGCUUUCAUUCAAGCAUUACCAUCUCAGCGAGACCUUCACUAGUUGCCCUAUUAAAAAUCGCAACCCCACCUCCUCCCCAACCCAUAUCCCUUUCCCCUCAUUGAUUUCUCCCCUUAGCACUCAUCAGCUUGUCACAUACUGUCAUUUGCUUAUUUGCUGGUUUAUUGUCUGUCUCCCUCCACCACAAUGACGGCUCCAUGAGAAAUGAUUUCUGUUUUGUCCGUGAUACGUUCUAGCAUCUAGGAUGCAGGCACAUGGUGGGCAGAUCUGCUGAAUGAAUGAGUGAAUAAGGUUCGGUUCCUUUAUUCCUCUUCUUUGCAGUGGAUAGUCAGAGUCCCUUCCUGAUAUCAGGGUACUGAGUAUGGGGUGAGACUCAGGCAUUAGAGUCCAGCACACUGCCCGCCAGUGCUGGCCAUCUCUGCUCCCAUCCCUGCUCAGCUCGCAUGCUUGGCUUCCCACCCAAGACAAGCAGCCCAGGAAACAGAUUCGAUCAAUGCUCUUCACCUUGAGCAUCUCGAGGGCUGUGCUUGACGAAGUCUUAAAGCCAAUAAAUAUCAGCAGCUAAGCUCUCUCUGCUAGACGGUCAGUGCAGAGGCAGCAGUGGCCACACUUAGGCAGCCGCUGGGGAGAGGACAAGGACAGUCAGCUUUAGAAGGAAGGACACAACUGACCCCGGCUUGCUGGCAGAUGAGGUGGGCUGAAGAGCUGGUGAAAACAGAGGCUCCCAGUUCCGUGUGUAAGAACAUGCAGGCUCAGUCAUACUGCAAGGGCCUGAGUCUUGGGUCUGUUGUAUCUGUGUGAUACUGGGUGUGCUGGUUAAUUGUAUGAGUCAACUUGGCCGGGCCAUAGUGCCCAGAGAUAUGGUCAGCAUGAUUCUGGAUGCUUCUGUGAGGGUGUUUUUGGAUGAGAUUAACAUCUAAGUUGGUGGACUUGAGCAGAGCAGGUUGCCCUCCAUAAUGUGGGUGGGCCUCGUCCAAUCAGUUGAAAGCCUGAACAGCAGAAAAAACUGACCUCCCCUAAGCAAGUGGGAUUUUGUCCACAGAUGGCCUUUAGGCUGGAGCUGCAGCCUCAGCUUUCCUCUGGGUCUCUAGCCUUCCUGCUUGCCCUGCAAAUUUUGGACUUCUUAGCCUCCUUAAAGUAAAUCUCUAUCAAUAUACCAGUGGCCCUCUGUAUCCAUGGUUCCGGAUCUGUGGAUUCAACCAACUGCAGAUCAAAAAUUUAGUUAAACCCAUGAAAGUUGUGUACAGCCUUUUUCCUUGUCGUGAUUCCCCAGACAAUACAUGUAACAAGUACUUAUAUAGCAUUUACACUGUAUUAUGUAUCAUAGGUAAACUAGAGAUGACUUAAAGCAGUGGUCCUCAACCUUUUUGGCACCAGGGACCGGUUGCAUGAAAGACAAUUUUUCCAUGAACUGGCAGGAGCGUGGUUUCAGGAUGAUUCAAACCAUUAUAUUUAUUGUGCACUUUAUUUCUAUUAUUAUUACAUUGUAAUAUAUAAUGAAAUAAUUAUACAUCUCACCAUAAUGUAGAUCAGUGGGAGCUCCAAGCUUGUCUUCCUGCAACUAGAUGGUCCCAUUUGGAGGUGAUGGGAGACAGUGACAGAUCAUCAGGCAUUGGAUUUUCAAAAGGAGCACGCAACCUAGAUCCCUCGCAUGUGCAGUUCACAGUAGGGUUUGUGCUCCUAAGAUAAUCUAAUGCCGCCACUGAUCUGACAGCAGGCAGAGCUCACACAGUAAUGCGAGCAAGCAAUGGGGAGCGGCUGUCAAUACAGAUGAAACUUCGCUCACUCACACAGCACUUAGCUCACUCACCUCCUGUUGUAUGGCCCAGUUCCUAACAGGCCAUAGGCCGGAUGGGUUUGUGGCCUAGGGGUUGGAGACCCCUGACUUAAAGUACAUAGGAGGAUGUGCUGUAGGUUAUAUGCAAAUACCACACCAUUUUAUUAUAUCUGCGAGGGGUCCUGGAACCAAUCUCCUGAAACCAAGGGAGGACCAUAUAUACACAUUCUAUUGGUUCUGUUUCCCUGGAGCGCCCUGGGUAAUACAAGGGAAGUCUUUUCAUGCCUUAGUGAACCUGGGACUCAGUUCGCUUGUCACUGGUGCAGCCUCCAGAGCCAGCUGAUGUAGGCCGCCACUCCCUCAAUGGCUCCUGGCCUUGGGCACAUAACUGAACCCCUACAUGCUCCAGGCUCCUCUGCAAAGUUGGGAGGGUAAUAACAGUAAUAACCACCCUCAGAGUGUUAUUGUGAGAAUUAAAUGCAUUUGUGCCCAUGAGUGCUGAAGGCUAGAGAUGCACUGGUCUUUACUAUCAGGACAUGAGGACUGAGAAAAUCCAUGCAACUGCUCAGCAUGGUAAGUAGCUUGCUAGGUGAGUGUGGCUCACACCAAGUUCUCAGCACCUGUUAGAUGAUACUAUUAACACAAUAUUUAUUUGUAAAUUACUGAAACCUUAUUCACCAGGUAAGUAUGAAUUGAACCCAGACCUACAAAAGCUUAAAAUACUUGAGGAACAAUAGUUUACCUUAUGAGGUAGUCAGCUGUCUGGUAACCUCAAUCAGCUAAAAUUUGCUGGCAAAUUCAGGAAUUGAAAAAUCCUAGAGAUUUGUCAGAGGGUACAAACUUGCAGUCAUGUAGGAUGAAUAAGUCUAACCUAAUGCACAGCAGGAGGACUAUGGUUCAUAAUAUUGUAUUGUAUGCUGAACAUUUGGUAAGAGACUGGAUUUUAUGUGUUCUUACCACACACACACACACACGCGGUAACUGUGUGAGGAGAUUCAUAUGUUAGUUUGUUUGACUGUAGUUGUCAUUUCACCAUGUGUAUCACAACAUCAUGCUGUAUACCUUAAAUAGAUACAAUAAUAAAUAAACAACUAUCCUAGAGAGAUAAGGGGUAAGCAUUAUACAAAGCCACACACGCAAUUUCGUGGAAAGGUUCAUGGGAUCCUCCUUAGGCCCCAUGGCCCCUUGAGCCUGCAGGCACAAUGUCUGUUGUAAAGGAAGCAUUGAAGAAUGGCCUACCUUGAAACCCCUUGGGAUUUUACGCUCAAUUUUGGAAGCCUGGCAUCCAUCCGAGUGCCCCUACAGGUAAGGACUUAUGCUUUUAUUGAAUUGCAUGUAAUGACAAGAAGUUAAUGUCGACUGAUGGACCUUAGAAACUAAAGAACUGGCUGGACAUGGUGACUCACACCUGUAAUCCCAACACUUUGGGAGGCCAAGGGCAGAUCACCUGAGGUCGGGAGUUCAAGACCAGCCUGGCCAACAUGGCGAAAUCCCGUCUCUACUAAAAGUUAAAAAAUUAGCCAGGCGUAGUGGUGGGCACCUGUAAUCCCAGCUACUCAGGAGGCUGAGGCAGGAGAAUCGCUUGCACCGGGAGGUGGAGGUUGCAGUGAGCCGAGAUUGCACCACUGCACUUCAGCCUGGGUGACAAUAGUGAGACUCCGUCAAAAAAAAAAAAAAAAAAAACCUAAAUAACUUAAUCAGUUCUUCCCAUUUCUGUAUCAUCAAGGGCAUUCAUGCAUCAUAUGUAAGUUCUGGAACACAAAUUUCCAAUUAAUAUUUUUUAUUCAAAAACAUAGGAUGGCAUAAAAACUCAGCCACAUGGGAACAUUCCUAAGUAUUAAGCUUCCAAUGUAUUUCAAUUUACAAGCAUUUAUUGAGCACCUACUAUGUGUCUAGAACCACAAUAAGUGAGAGGAUGUUUUAAGAUAUGUUCUUAGUCUGAAGGAGCUCACAGUCUAGCCAGGUUCACAUAUUUCACAAUAUUUAUUGGCAUGUGAGAAAAUAACAAACUGCUAUAAAACUUCAUAGUUGGGUGAGACCACUGUGGGUUGUAGAAAUAAGGAAAGGAUUCUUCGGGGAGGUAAAAAGCGAAUUGAAUUAUAUCACGAAGACUUGGUUGUUGUCUUGGAGGUAAAUAUAGCACCUAUUUCUUCAUCUCCUAAUUUUGAACCAAUUAAGACACAGGAGCGAGACAGAUGAGGAUGAAAAUAUCACACUAAAAGGCUGAAUUGACCCAUGUACCUGAGGUGGGUAGCCAUAUGGGAUUCCUCCUACUUUACCCCCUGAAUGAGGUAGCCUCAUUCUCCCAGUCACAUGUACCAUUGACCAGCAUAGAUUUCUGAAAGGGAUGGCUGAGAGGAGUGUGCCCCAUUCAGCAAGGAGGCAGAGGCUACAGAUGGCUCUCAAAAUCUCUCCCGGAGAGUGGAAUGGAAAUUCUCGGCCUCCGUGGAAACAUGAGGGGUAAGCUAUAUAUAUAUCCUUGUACGAC